GGUAUACCUCUAGUUUGGAGCUGUGCUGUAAAAACAAGAGUAACAUUUUUAUAUUAAAGUUAAAUAAAGUUACAACUUUGAAGAGAGUUUCUGCAAGACAUGACACAAAGCUGCUAGCAGAAAAUCAAAACGCUGAUUAAAAGAAGCACGGUAUGAUGACCAAACAUAAAAAGUGUUUUAUAAUUGUUGGUGUUUUAAUAACAACUAAUAUUAUUACUCUGAUAGUUAAACUAACUCGAGAUUCUCAGAGUUUAUGCCCCUAUGAUUGGAUUGGUUUCCAAAACAAAUGCUAUUAUUUCUCUAAAGAAGAAGGAGAUUGGAAUUCAAGUAAAUACAACUGUUCCACUCAACAUGCCGACCUAACUAUAAUUGACAACAUAGAAGAAAUGAAUUUUCUUAGGCGGUAUAAAUGCAGUUCUGAUCACUGGAUUGGACUGAAGAUGGCAAAAAAUCGAACAGGACAAUGGGUAGAUGGAGCUACAUUUACCAAAUCGUUUGGCAUGAGAGGGAGUGAAGGAUGUGCCUACCUCAGCGAUGAUGGUGCAGCAACAGCUAGAUGUUACACCGAAAGAAAAUGGAUUUGCAGGAAAAGAAUACACUAAGUUAAUGUCUAAGAUAAUGGGGAAAAUAGAAAAUAACAUUAUUAAGUGUAAAACCAGCAAAGUACUUUUUUAAUUAAACAAAGUUCGAGUUUUGUACCUGUCUGGUUAAUUCUGCUUACGUGUCAGGCUACACAUAAAAGCCACUUCAAAGAUUGGCAAAAAAUGGUUACAGGUAUUCUGCUGAGUUUUUUUCUUUCUUUCUUUCUCUCUCUCUCUUUCUUUCUUUCUUUCUUUCUUUCUUUUUUUAACUGUAAACCAGAAAACAAUUGUGGGGAUCAAGGACAGACAUAGCACUUAGACAGGACUUUCAUGACCCAAUAUGGAACAAUUUGAGUACCAGAAUAGGAGAUUAUGGCCUAUUGAACAAAAUGUGAAACUGGGAGUCCACAAAGACAUAAAUGGAAAGAUGAAGUACCUCCUGACAGAGCAAGAAUGGCACUGAACAAUGUUAUAUGGACAAUGGCUAUUUUAUUCAAGACUAUUACAAUAGGGAAAAGAGACUAGGACUCAGUCUGAACUGAAAUCUGUCAAAACAAAGGGGGGUGGGGCUUUAAGAGUGAAGGUGAGGAGGAGAUCACACACCGUAUGUGUUUGCUAACUGGCUUUACCCAAAAGAAAAUUAAACUUUCUUUGAUCUGUACAAGUUGAUCAAACAAAUGGGGUCAUUCUUGUCAUAUGCAACUAAAACAGGGUAGACAGGCCAGGGGAAAAAGGCACUCAGGGCACACAGCAUUGCUUCAAAAUAUAAUUCUCUACAAACCUAGUUGCUAAAACUACCUGUUGUAACCUAAAACCAGUUUUAUCUAACAGCUAUUAAAACAACCUACUGUGACUGCAAAACUGGUUUUACCCACCACUGUCACACACCAAUCAGAACUUGCCAGCUCCUCAAAACUUUACUAGGGCCAAUAAACUUUCUUUCAAAACAAUA